AGAGUCUCGAGUGGAGAGAGGCCGGACAUCGGUGGCCGAAGUCUGAGAGAGAAGCUGGCCCUCAGCGGCUGGGUCGGUAGGAAUUAGGGCAGAGUUAGGAGCGGCCUGCGGAGGGGCCCGCUCAGGCCGAUGCCGGUAGUGGAAACAGAGGAAGCCACCGCCGCGCUCUUCUCGGAACUGGCUAAAAUAGCUCCGUAAAUGGGCCGAGCGCAACACGGAGGGGAUACCGCUCACUACCAGGUAAACUGUCGCCUCCUCCUCCGCCUCGCCGGGCACCGCCAUCUUGGAUUGUCACAUGAUCAGCUAGAACCAAGUCUCGCGAGAACACCGCGAGCAACGUUCCAGCCCCUGCGUUGCGAGAUUGUGAAAAUUCUAACUAGUCCUUUGGGAUUGGGGUUGUGGAACCUGGAGCUGGAAGAUCCGAAGUCUUCUGUGUUCCUUUCCCACAGAGGGAAGCCGGCGAUGAUGGAAAAACUCACCUGGAAAAUGGGGUCAUAGAGUUCUUUCAUAAAGCUCUCAUGAGGACCAAAUAAGAAGCCUGCGGGAGGGGUCAUUUUUGAGGUAUUUAGUUGUGGAUAUUGCACACCUAAUCUCAACCUUCCUCAGUUCUGAACCUUUAGUCGUUCUUCCAUUUAUUUUUCCAAAAUGUGUUGAUGAACUCCCACAAAUCGGUAAGAAAAAGAUAACCCGGUAGAAAAAUGGGCCGAAGAUACUUCGCAAAAGAGGAAACACGCAGGUCCAAUUUACAAUGAAAGUGCUAUGAGUUACUAGAGGCUUACGUUAAAGAAAAGAUGCACAACUCAAUAAUAAAAGAAAUGCAGCGAGACCCACUUUGCAUCCACUAUGUUGGCAAACUUUAAAACCUUAGAGUCGAUGACAACAUGGUGGAACUGAAGCUCUCAUACACUGUUGGUGGAAAUCUUCCCGAACUUUGGCUUACCCUCAGCUUGAGCCAGCGCACAUCUCCUCCUUAACAGCCUCUCCUGAGAAUAGGCUGGCUUCAAGGAAUGGGGGAAGUGAAUGAUCUCAAACUACAGAAAUGGCAGUGAACUUGUCUGUUUCAAUUCGGGAGUGGGCUGCUUCCUGAUUGGCUGUGAUUGGGCUUUCACUGUGCUUGUGAACACCUUCUUCAGCUUCCUUCGACGCAAAACAGACUUUUUCAUUGGAGGAGAAGAAGGGAUGGCAGAGAAGCUUAUCACACAGACUUUCAGCCACCACAAUCAGCUGGCACAGAAGACCCGGCGGGAGAAGAGAGCCCGGCAGGAGGCCGAGCGGCGGGAGAAGGCGGAGCGGGCGGCCAGACUGGCCAAGGAAGCCAAGUCAGAGACCUCAGGGCCCCAGAUCAAGGAGCUAACUGAUGAAGAGGCAGAGAGGCUGCAGCUAGAGAUUGACCAGAAAAAGGAUGCAGAGAAUCAUGAGGCCCAGCUCAAGAACGGCAGCCUUGACUCCCCAGGGAAGCAGGAUACUGAGGAAGAUGAGGAGGAAGAUGAGAAGGACAAAGGAAAACUGAAGCCCAACCUAGGCAACGGGGCAGACCUGCCCAAUUACCGCUGGACCCAGACCCUGUCGGAGCUGGACCUGGCGGUCCCUUUCUGUGUGAACUUCCGGCUGAAAGGGAAGGACAUGGUGGUGGACAUCCAGCGGCGGCACCUCCGGGUGGGGCUCAAGGGGCAGCCAGCGAUCAUUGAUGGGGAGCUCUACAAUGAAGUGAAGGUGGAGGAGAGCUCGUGGCUCAUUGAGGACGGCAAGGUGGUGACUGUGCAUCUGGAGAAGAUCAAUAAGAUGGAGUGGUGGAGCCGCUUGGUGUCCAGUGACCCUGAGAUCAACACCAAGAAGAUUAACCCUGAGAAUUCCAAGCUGUCAGACCUGGACAGUGAGACUCGCAGCAUGGUGGAAAAGAUGAUGUAUGACCAGCGACAGAAGUCCAUGGGGCUGCCAACUUCAGACGAACAGAAGAAACAGGAGAUUCUGAAGAAGUUCAUGGAUCAACAUCCGGAGAUGGAUUUUUCCAAGGCUAAAUUCAACUAGCCCCUGUUUUUUCCUCCCUGAACUCUUGGGGCUGAGCUGCAACCACCCAACUUUCUUUCCCACUCUUCUCUGGGACUUGUGGGCCUCAGGGCUUGGGGCAGGCAUGGGACUGGCCCAGGCACACAGGUCCCGGGGCAUCAGGAGAAAGGCUGGGUCUUGGGACCUUGUCCUCCCCAGUUGGCCUACUGUUACACAUUAAAACGAUUUGCCCAGCUCCUUCUGUGUCCUCUCUUGCCUCUGGCCUUUCUCUGGGGCACAGGCCUCUUACGGCUGCUGCUGGGAACUGGGAGUUUGGCUUCUAGCCCAGAUUCUGCCAUGUGACCUAGGGCACAUCCUUGCCCCUCUCUGGGCCUCAGUUUCUCAUUACUUAAAGAUUAAAACAAGGCUUGGCCGGGUGUGAUGGUUCAUGUCUGUAAUCCCAGCACUUUGGGAGGCUGAGGGGAGCAGAUCACCUGAUGUCAGGAGUUUGAGACCAGCUUGGCCAACAUGGAGAAACCCAGUCUCUACUAAAAAUACAAAAAUUAGCCGGGUGUGGUGGUGCACACCUGUAAUCCCAGCUACUCGGGAGGCUGAGGCAGGAGAAUCGCUUGAACCCGGGUGGCGGAGGUUGCAGUGAGCCGAGAUUGCACUACUUCACUCCAGCAUGGGUGACAGAGACUCCAUCUCAAAAAAAUAAAUAAAUAAAACAAG